ACUCUAGCGACGGCGGGGAAGAGUGUGUACGUGGUGGGGGCUUCCUCGGUGGCGGGCAUGGAGGCUUCGCGCUGCCGGCUCAGUCCCAGCGGCGACAGUGUCUUCCAUGAAGAAAUGAUGAAGAUGCGACAGGCUAAGCUGGAUUAUCAGAGGCUACUACUUGAGAAGAGGCAAAGGAAAAAGCGCCUUGAGCCAUUUAUGGUGCAGCCCAAUCCAGAAGCCAGGCUACGUCGGGCAAAGCCAAGGGCCAGUGAUGAGCAGACUCCCUUGGUGAACUGUCAUACUCCCCACAGCAAUGUCAUCUUACAUGGUAUUGAUGGUCCAGCUGCUGUCCUGAAACCAGACGAAGUUCAUGCUCCAUCAGUAAGCUCCUCUGUUGUGGAAGAAGAUGCUGAAAACACCGUGGAUACUGCUUCCAAGCCAGGACUUCAGGAGCGUCUCCAAAAGCAUGAUAUCUCUGAAAGUGUGAACUUCGAUGAGGAGACUGAUGGAAUAUCCCAGUCAGCAUGUUUAGAAAGACCCAAUUCUGCAUCAAGCCAGAAUUCAACCGAUACAGGCACUUCCGGUUCUGCUACUGCCGCCCAACCAGCUGAUAACCUCCUGGGAGACAUAGACGACCUGGAGGACUUUGUGUAUAGUCCUGCCCCUCAAGGUGUCACAGUAAGAUGUCGGAUAAUCCGGGAUAAAAGGGGAAUGGAUCGGGGUCUCUUCCCCACCUACUAUAUGUACUUGGAAAAAGAAGAAAAUCAGAAGAUAUUUCUUCUUGCAGCUAGAAAGCGGAAAAAGAGCAAAACAGCCAACUACCUUAUCUCCAUUGAUCCAGUUGAUUUAUCUCGUGAAGGAGAAAGUUAUGUCGGCAAGCUUAGAUCCAACCUCAUGGGGACCAAGUUUACAGUUUAUGACCGUGGCAUCUGCCCCAUGAAGGGCCGGGGUUUGGUAGGAGCGGCCCACACCCGGCAGGAGCUGGCUGCCAUCUCCUAUGAAACAAACGUACUUGGAUUUAAAGGUCCUAGGAAAAUGUCUGUGAUCAUUCCUGGAAUGACACUGAAUCAUAAGCAGAUCCCCUAUCAGCCACAAAACAACCAUGACAGUUUGCUCUCAAGGUGGCAGAACAGAACUAUGGAAAAUCUGGUUGAGCUGCACAACAAGGCCCCCGUCUGGAACAGUGACACUCAGUCCUAUGUCCUCAACUUCCGUGGCCGGGUCACUCAGGCGUCUGUGAAGAACUUCCAGAUAGUCCACAAAAAUGACCCUGAUUAUAUAGUCAUGCAGUUUGGACGUGUGGCAGAUGACGUGUUCACACUGGAUUACAACUACCCACUUUGUGCAGUACAGGCCUUUGGCAUCGGUCUUUCUAGCUUUGACAGUAAGCUGGCGUGUGAAUGAGAGAACAGUCAGGCAGGGAGCCCUUCUCCCCACAGAGCUUUCAGGAGCAGACAGUGGCCUCCCCUUCCCCUCCCUGCCCCAGGACUUAAAGAGCAAUAGUUUGCCCCUUUUGGAAUGAUCUCUGAAUAUAUAAAACACACACACAAAGAGCAAUAGUUUGCCCCUUUUGGAACGACCCCUGAAUAUAUAAAACACACACACGAAGAGCAAUAGUUUGCCCCUUUUGGAACGACCCCUGAAUAUAUAAAACACACACGAAGAGCAAUAGUUUGCCCCUUUUGGAACGACCCCUGAAUAUAUAAAACACACACACGAAGAGCAAUAGUUUGCCCCUUUUGGAACGACCCCUGAAUAUAUAAAACACACACACACCCCGCGCACUCUCACUCCUUUUCCAGGUUUCAUAGACUUGGUGAGGGAUCACAGCUUAGCAUGGGUGAGAGAUGAUUUAAAGCACAGGGAGAUUCUUGUCACAUUGGGGUCUCCAAAGCUAGAAUGGGAUUUCAUGUGCUUGGAAACUUGCAGUAGAAUCAGGGACUGACAUCGCAGUUCCUCUCCUCUCUUCAUUCCCUCACAGCAGAUUGGCCGGCACCAAUCUUAGUCAAGAGUGGCUGUGAUCACAUUUGUGAUCAAUUAUGUGAGAAUUUUAUAUAAUUGUCUUCAUUUCAAUUAAGGCUGAAAGCAUAAACUCUAGAGGUGACUCAGUCAGGACUGACAGUAAUGUGAUAAUUGCCUUCAUUUUCAACCCAGGAGUGCCUCUCACAGCUAUAUGACUACGGAUCCAUUAGUGAGGAGCGACACACACACCUGUAGGCAUCCUGUGCAAACACUUUGUCAUUAUCAAGAGAGAUGGCAGUAUUGACCAUUUAGUUUAGUUAAAAAAAAAAAAAAAAAGGUGGCAGGAGAGGCUUUGGGGAGGAUCAGCCAGCAGACAUGAGCACUGCUGGCCCGUGUGGCAGAGCUGUGGACUUUCUUCUCGGCUCCCUCAACCCUGGCUCAGGCACAGAAGGUGUUUUGCUACGUUUUUUUGAUUAUUACACCCCUCCACGUAUUAUGUGACUCUUACACCAGUUCACCCUUCCCAGAAUGUAUCCAAACCUUGAGAAUGCAGGAGCUCUGUGAGCUCCACCGUCAGCACCAUUCAGCUGCAUCCCUUGUGCACAGAACUGUUUGCCAGCGUUGGGUGGGACACCCGUGGCGGCUGCUCCCUCAGACCUCCCUUCUGUGGACUGACCUCUCACCUCCGCCUGUUGUUCCUGCACCACAUCAGAUAAGCAUGUGAAGGAGGGCCAACUGGCAGCUGCGGGACCCUUGGCUUGUCCCCCACCGACAAGUCCCACCUGCUGGGUGAGGACGAGACUGUUUCCAUCUCAGGCAUGUAUCCCACCAAGUGCCUCCCUCACAGCCAUGCCCAGAAGCCUCACACCUCGUCACCACCACCACCCCCCACCCCAUCCUGAGGCACUGCCUGGCAGAUAACCCUGGUUGGCCACAGAAGCUAUUAAUACACGACAGCAUGUGGGGAAGGACUUAUGGUGGGCCAGGUGGACCUCAUCCUGCUUCUUCCUCCCUCUGGUUUAAAGAGAUAUAUAAACUAAUUUCACAUAAUUUGUGUGUGCAGGUGAUUGGUUUUUACAUAAGUCCUAUUUAUACCUUUUAUAUGUUACAGAAAUAAAAGUUAAUUUAUAUAAAAA